GACCCCGCCCCCGAGGCGAGGAGUUUGCGGCGGCUUCGAGUCUCGGGCUCCGGCGUUUGGGCGGCUUGUCUUCCCUGCCCGCCACAGUCGCGGCCCCUGGGACCAGGGCGAGGCCGGAACCCCGGCCGAGAGCACCUCCCUGCUAUCAUCUGUCCCCAAACUUUCCCUCAAUCGAGGCGCCGGCGGGGCGGCCCGGCGGCCGGAAGUGCACCCUGCUCGGGCUUUGCGCCCCCGGCAGCUUCCUCCGCCCGCGAGGGCCCCGCGCCUUCCCAUUUUCCCAACCGGCAAACUGAGCCUCGGCCACCCGGCCCACUUGCCGGUCGGAAGUCAGGACGUCGCCGCUUGCGGCGGCGUGGAAGGCUUCGCCUCCGGAGCAAGGAGGACGGGCCGCUGGUUAGCGGGCCCUUUGCCCGAGGGUGUGGACCUCUACCCGCUCCCCUGCCCCUUCCCGCAGCCUUCUUCCCCUCCCGAGGACAGGCCUAGGGGGUGCAAAUGCCAGGGCUUCCGUUAGGUCUCCUUAGUCUAGGGCUGCAGGGGUUGGGGGACGAAGACGUGUAGACGGGGCCACCCGUCUAUGGCUUCCAGGGUGGCAGCGGCCCUGGCCACGUGAUUGAGGGGCCCAGUGCAAAAUGAAGAUGCCAGGCCCCUUGUUAAGUUUUUGAGAAUUUCACACGGUAACAGCAGAGUAUUCAACCUGGUGCGGGGUCCCUGACUUGCUUGCAGGACUGUAGUCUGGGUAACGGGCUGGGACCCUCCAUCACAAAGGGUGAUUCUUGUUUUUCAUCGUCAGUGUCAUUUGCCUUCUUCAGGGCUUCCAGGUGGAUCUUCGUCACCACCCUAGGAUUGCUCACCAUUCUCAAGCUUGAAAACCCACCUGCAAUCAUUUGGGCGGGGGGGGGGGGGCAUCUUUAAGCGCCCAGGUGAACUUGGUCUGCAGGCAGCAGCUGUCCUUUUCUCUGGAUCUUCUGCUGAGGUCGGUAGGUUGAUAAGUGAUACUGAUUUUGUGGCAGGAACUCCCUUCAGCCAACUCCUGUCUUCCUGGGAAGGCCUCUGGAAGAAACCAGGAUUUUGACACCAUGGUCCCCCGAUAGACUUGCCCAGGUGGCUUUGCUUUGCCCAGUUGAAUGUGAGCAGAAGUGAUGAGUAUCACUUCCAAGCAAAAGUGUAAGAGCCAGUGUGGUGGCUGCUUCUGUCCUUCCCCUUUGCUGCAAGAAGAACAGCAAUGCCCCAUAGACAGGUUGGCCUGAGUUUCAGAGGGAAGGCUCCAUGUUACAUAACUGCAGCCCAUCUGCACUGUCCGCGGAACUGGAGUGCAAAACAAACCUUUAUCAUUGUAAGCCACUAACGUUUGGGGUUGUUACGAAAGCAUAACACCACCUAAGCGGCUUCAACACUCCCACAAGUUUAAGAGGAAAAGGAGUUUAUUAAAGGACACCAGAUGGCUCACAGGAUCUCCAAGAAGGCCUCGGUGACUCCAAAGCCAGGAAUGAUGUCCAAAUCUCACUGAGGGACUGCACCAGCGCAGGUGCGCACUGCUGCCUCCUCUGAGUACAUAUUUAGUAAGUCACACCAGUGUUGGAGCCCAGAAUCUUGACCACUGCUGUCUCUGGAAACUGGACACCUCUGCCACUAACCUUGGCAGUAGAUGGCCUUUGGGAGCCCUCCACGUCUUCAGGUUGCCCUCUUCUGGAUUGAAGUCGCUGGCAGAGCUGAGUUUACCUGCCUGUGCUCUUGCUAUCAAAGAGGCUGGAAAAGCAAAUUUCUUGUUUCUACUUUGGCGAGUUAGGAGUCAAACAGGAGGAAUUACCAAGACAUAGGGAGGAGGUUCAGAAGUUAGUGAAUGACCAUGAAGCAUGAAAGACGUCCACGACCUGCUGGAGACCUGAGGAUGGAGCGGACACCAAGGGAUCCCAGCUGAGCAAUAGAGCAGCUGGGUGCCAUGACUUACGCCCCGGCCCCAGUCAUGCAUAUACCAUUGACUCUUCAGUUAUUUGAGGAAACCAUUCCUAGCUUUGCUUAAGCCAGCUGGAAUGGGCUUACUGACACUUGCAAUGGAAAGAGUCCUAAUGAUCUGUGUCUCAAAUGGAUGAGCGUUGGCACAGUGGCUAACGGUGGUGCCCUGGCUCGGAUGCCUGAAAGUUUUGGUUGUUCUCAGUCCCCAGUAAGUGGGGAUGAGGCUGACAGUUAUGGGAAUGGCCGCUUCUGGUAGGUAUCAGAAAGAAUCUUGUAGUUGCCUGUGGCAGAAGAUCCGACCCAAACUGAGCAAAACCAGUUUCAAACGAAUCUGGUUUGAAACUUCCGAAGGUAUUGUCAUAUCUGCAUCCUACAUUGUGAGGUCACCAAGGCAACCUAUUAAUCAUUCUAGAAUCUACCUCUUGAAGAUUACAAAUGAGACUGGGAAACCCUCUUCAAUAAGACCUGUGUGAUGAUAGAUUGUGUCCUGAGCCCGCAGGUCAGGCUGAAAGAGUCAACAACCAGCAAAGUGAAGAUCUAGGAGUCUGUUCCCCUUGAACCUGUGUGGACCUGAUCAAACCUCGAGGGAAAGGCUGGGAGAACACAUCCCUGGUCAGCUGUAGGAAAGCCAGAGAGCAUUUGAGAAGAGGCUGAAGCUUGAAUUUUGCAAACACACAAGCCCUCUGCAUUUCCCCAGAGAGAAGGUUUUUUUCUCGUCUUCAUUUCCUUUGAAACACCUGGGGUGAGGAAAAACCUCUACAUUGGCCAAGCAGAAGAAACAGAAUCUAUGACUGAAGAGGAUCGGCUAAGAGUGGUUCCUCGCAGCUUAAAGGGAGGCACUUUUCACACUCUGUCUUAAAAUCAGAAGUUGAAUUCAUGAACACAUAUGAUUUAGAUAGAAGUCAUGGGAUGCAGCAGUUCUUCAACGAAAACCAGGAGAUCUGACACAUCACUGAGAGCUGCGUUGAUCAUCCAGAACUGGUACCGAGGUUACAAAGCUCGACUGAAGGCCAGACAACACUAUGCCCUCACCAUCUUCCAGUCCAUCGAAUAUGCUGAUGAACAAGGCCAAAUGCAGUUAUCCACCUUCUUUUCCUUCAUGUUGGAAAACUACACACAUAUACAUAAGGAAGAGCUAGAAUUAAGAAAUCAGUCUCUUGAAAGCGAACAGGACAUGAGGGAUAGAUGGGAUUAUGUGGACUCGAUAGAUGUCCCAGACUCCUAUAAUGGUCCUCGGCUACAAUUUCCUCUCACUUGUACGGAUAUUGAUUUACUUCUUGAGGCCUUCAAGGAACAACAGAUACUUCAUGCCCAUUAUGUCUUAGAGGUGCUAUUUGAAACCAAGAAAGUCCUGAAGCAAAUGCCGAAUUUCACUCACAUACAAACUUCUCCCUCCAAAGAGGUAACAAUCUGUGGUGAUUUGCAUGGGAAACUGGAUGAUCUUUUUUUGAUCUUCUACAAGAAUGGUCUCCCCUCAGAGAGGAACCCGUAUGUUUUUAAUGGUGACUUUGUAGAUCGAGGAAAGAAUUCCAUAGAGAUCCUAAUGAUCCUGUGUGUGAGUUUUCUUGUCUACCCCAAUGACCUGCACUUGAACAGAGGGAACCACGAAGAUUUUAUGAUGAAUCUGAGGUAUGGCUUCACGAAAGAAAUUUUGCAUAAAUAUAAGCUACAUGGAAAAAGAAUCUUACAAAUCUUGGAAGAAUUCUAUGCCUGGCUCCCAAUCGGUACAAUCGUUGACAAUGAAAUCCUGGUCAUCCAUGGUGGGAUAUCAGAGACCACAGACUUGAAUUUACUCCACCGUGUAGAGAGGAACAAGAUGAAAUCUGUGCUGAUACCACCAACGGAAACAAACAGAGACCAUGACACUGACUCGAAGCACAAUAAAGUAGGUGUGACUUUUAAUGCACAUGGAAGAAUCAAAACAAAUGGAUCUCCUACUGAACACUUAACAGAGCAUGAAUGGGAACAGAUUAUUGAUAUUCUGUGGAGUGAUCCCAGAGGCAAAAAUGGCUGUUUUCCAAAUACGUGCCGAGGAGGGGGCUGCUAUUUUGGACCAGAUGUUACUUCCAAGAUUCUUAAUAAAUACCAGUUGAAGAUGCUCAUCAGGUCUCAUGAAUGUAAGCCCGAAGGGUAUGAAAUCUGUCAUGAUGGGAAGGUGGUGACUAUAUUUUCUGCUUCUAAUUAUUAUGAAGAAGGCAGCAAUCGAGGAGCUUACAUCAAACUAUGUUCUGGUACAACUCCUCGAUUUUUCCAGUACCAAGUAACUAAAGCAACGUGCUUUCAGCCUCUUCGCCAAAGAGUGGAUACUAUGGAAAACAGCGCCAUCAAGAUAUUAAGAGAGAGAGUGAUUUCACGAAAAAGUGACCUUACUCGUGCUUUCCAACUUCAAGACCACAGAAAAUCAGGAAAACUUUCUGUGAGCCAGUGGGCUUUUUGCAUGGAGAACAUUUUGGGGCUGAACUUACCAUGGAGAUCCCUCAGUUCGAAUCUGGUAAACAUAGACCAAAAUGGAAACGUUGAAUACAUGUCCAGCUUCCAGAAUAUCCGCAUUGAAAAACCUGUACAAGAGGCUCAUUCUACUCUAGUUGAAACUCUGUACAGAUACAGAUCUGACCUGGAAAUCAUAUUUAAUGCCAUUGACACUGAUCACUCAGGCCUGAUCUCCGUGGAAGAAUUUCGUGCCAUGUGGAAACUUUUUAGUUCUCACUACAAUGUUCACAUUGAUGAUUCCCAAGUCAAUAAGCUUGCCAACAUAAUGGACUUGAACAAAGAUGGAAGCAUUGACUUUAAUGAGUUUUUAAAGGCUUUCUAUGUAGUGCAUAGAUAUGAAGACUUGAUGAAACCUGAUGUCACCAACCUUGGCUAAACACAAAUGAGAGCUUCCCUCAGGCUCCCUGAAACAGCUAGGCCCAAAUCACAAGUACAGUCCUUUCCAACACCCCUGAAAUUCAUAGUCAGUAGCAGAGAAAAGCAGAUCCCAAUUCAUCCCACAAACAGAUGCAUAGUAUGGGUUUUGGAAGUCCCUAGCAAGCUGUUAUUGGUAAGAUUAGGUUAAAUGUCAGUAAUAGGAUUUGGUUUCAGCAUUAGUACCUACAUAUUGCCAGUGAGAAACUGGGUUGGACCUAGUGGUGUUGUCGUGAGUGCCACCUAACCAGGAGGCCAGAGCGGUUUGAAAACAUCCUGAAAGGAACUCAUACAGCACAAGAGAAAACUACUAAGCUUGACAUCUGUGAGUGACUGAGGGAGACAGGAGGAAUACCAGGUUAUUCAUGGAAUAAAGUCUUUCCAUCUUUAAA